GUUGUGUCCACUAACCGGACUCAGAAGGGACUUCCCUGCUCGGCUGGCUUUCGGUUUCUCUGCUCACCUCCGGAUAAAUCACGGGGUCUCCCGCGCCGCUCAUGGCGCCUCCCGUCCGUCUCGAGCGUCCCUUUCCUUCCCGGCGCUUUCCUGGGUUGCUUCUGGCGGCCCUGGUGUUGCUGCUGUCCUCCUUCUCCGAUCAAUGCAAUGUCCCGGAAUGGCUUCCAUUUGCCAGGCCUACCAACCUAACUGAUGACUUUGAGUUUCCCAUUGGGACAUAUCUGAACUAUGAAUGCCGCCCUGGUUAUUCCGGAAGACCGUUUUCUAUCAUCUGCCUAAAAAACUCAGUCUGGACAAGUGCUAAGGACAAGUGCAAACGUAAAUCAUGUCGUAAUCCUCCAGAUCCUGUGAAUGGCAUGGCACAUGUGAUCAAAGACAUCCAGUUCAGAUCCCAAAUUAAAUAUUCUUGUCCUAAAGGAUACCGACUCAUUGGUUCCUCGUCUGCCACAUGCAUCAUCUCAGGCAACACUGUCAUUUGGGAUAAUAAAACACCUGUUUGUGACAGAAUUAUUUGUGGGCUACCCCCCACCAUCGCCAAUGGAGAUUUCACUAGCAUCAGCAGAGAGUAUUUUCACUAUGGAUCAGUGGUGACCUACCACUGCAAUCUUGGAAGCAGAGGGAAAAAGGUGUUUGAGCUUGUGGGUGAGCCCUCCAUAUACUGCACCAGCAAAGAUGAUCAAGUGGGCAUCUGGAGUGGCCCAGCCCCUCAGUGCAUUAUACCUAACAAAUGCACGCCUCCAAAUGUGGAAAAUGGAAUAUUGGUAUCUGACAACAGAAGCUUAUUUUCCUUAAAUGAAGUUGUGGAGUUUAGGUGUCAGCCUGGCUUUGGCAUGAAAGGGCCCUCCCAUGUGAAGUGCCAGGCCCUGAACAAAUGGGAGCCAGAGUUACCAAGCUGCUCCAGGGUAUGUCAGCCACCUCCAGAUGUCCUGCAUGCUGAGCGUACCCAAAGGGACAAGGACAACUUUUCACCCGGGCAGGAAGUGUUCUACAGCUGUGAGCCCGGCUACGACCUCAGAGGAUCUACGUAUUUGCACUGCACACCCCAGGGAGACUGGAGCCCUGCAGCCCCCAGAUGUGAAGUGAAAUCCUGUGAUGACUUCCUGGGCCAACUUCCUAAUGGCCAUGUGCUAUUUCCACUUAAUCUCCAGCUUGGAGCAAAAGUGGAUUUUGUUUGUGAUGAAGGAUUUCAAUUAAAAGGCAGCUCUGCUAGUUACUGUGUUUUGGCUGGAAUGGAAAGCCUUUGGAAUAGCAGUGUUCCAGUGUGUGAACGUAAAUCAUGUGAAACUCCUCCAGUUCCAGUGAAUGGCAUGGUGCAUGUGAUCACAGACAUCCAUGUUGGAUCCAGAAUCAACUAUUCUUGUACUACAGGGCACCGACUCAUUGGUCACUCAUCUGCUGAAUGUAUCCUCUCGGGCAAUACUGCCCAUUGGAGCAUGAAGCCACCAAUUUGUCAACAAAUCUUUUGUCCAAAUCCUCCAGCUAUCCUUAAUGGGAGACACACAGGAACUCCCCUUGGAGAUAUUCCCUAUGGAAAAGAAGUAUCUUACACAUGUGACCCCCACCCAGACAGAGGGAUGACCUUCAACCUCAUUGGGGAGAGCACCAUCCGCCGCACAAGUGAACCUCAUGGGAAUGGGGUUUGGAGCAGCCCUGCCCCUCGCUGUGAACUUCCUGUUGGUGCUGGUUCACAUGAUGCUCUUAUAGUUGGUAAGUUUUAUGAAGUGUUUGCUGAGGAAUUCUGUCAUCUUUAACAGUAAGUACCUACUUAU